AUGAGAAGAAACUGCACGUUGGUGACUGAGUUCAUUCUCCUGGGACUGACCAGUCGCCGGGAAUUACAAAUUCUCCUCUUCACGCUGUUUCUGGCCAUUUACAUGGUCACGGUGGCAGGGAACCUUGGCAUGAUUGUCCUCAUCCAGGCCAACGCCUGGCUCCACAUGCCCAUGUACUUUUUCCUGAGCCACUUAUCCUUCGUGGAUCUGUGCUUCUCUUCCAAUGUGACUCCAAAGAUGCUGGAGAUUUUCCUUUCAGAGAAGAAAAGCAUUUCCUAUCCUGCCUGUCUUGUGCAGUGUUACCUUUUUAUCGCCUUGGUCCAUGUUGAGAUCUACAUCCUGGCUGUGAUGGCCUUUGACCGGUACAUGGCCAUCUGCAACCCUCUGCUUUAUGGCAGCAGAAUGUCCAAGAGUGUGUGCUCCUUCCUCAUCACGGUGCCUUAUGUGUAUGGAGCGCUCACUGGCCUGAUGGAGACCAUGUGGACCUACAACCUAGCCUUCUGUGGCCCCAAUGAAAUUAAUCACUUCUACUGUGCGGACCCACCACUGAUUAAGCUGGCUUGUUCUGACACCUACAACAAGGAGUUGUCAAUGUUUAUUGUGGCUGGCUGGAACCUUUCUUUUUCUCUCUUCAUCAUAUGUAUUUCCUACCUUUACAUUUUCCCUGCUAUUUUAAAGAUUCGCUCUACAGAGGGCAGGCAAAAAGCUUUUUCUACCUGUGGCUCCCAUCUGACAGCUGUCACUAUAUUCUAUGCAACCCUUUUCUUCAUGUAUCUCAGACCCCCCUCAAAGGAAUCUGUUGAACAGGGUAAAAUGGUAGCUGUAUUUUAUACCACAGUAAUCCCUAUGCUGAACCUUAUAAUUUAUAGCCUUAGAAAUAAAAAUGUAAAAGAAGCAUUAAUCAAAGAGCUGUCAAUGAAGAUAUACUUUUCUUAA